AUCCCGAGUCCCGGGCUCAGUAUGUGGCGCCUUCCUCGCGCGCUGUGUGUGCACGCUGCAAAGACCAGCAAGCUCUCUGGACCUUGGAGCAGGCCUGCCGCCUUCAUGUCCACUCUCCUCAUCAAUCAGCCCCAGUAUGCGUGGCUGAAAGAGCUGGGGCUCCGCGAGGAAAACGAGGGCGUGUAUAAUGGAAGCUGGGGAGGCCGGGGAGAGGUUAUUACGACCUAUUGCCCUGCUAACAACGAGCCAAUAGCAAGAGUCCGACAGGCCAGUGUGGCAGACUAUGAAGAAACUGUAAAGAAAGCAAGAGAAGCAUGGAAAAUCUGGGCAGAUAUUCCUGCUCCAAAACGAGGAGAAAUAGUAAGACAGAUUGGCGAUGCCUUGCGGGAGAAGAUCCAAGUACUAGGAAGCUUGGUGUCUUUGGAGAUGGGGAAAAUCUUAGUGGAAGGUGUGGGUGAAGUUCAGGAGUAUGUGGAUAUCUGUGACUAUGCUGUUGGUUUAUCAAGGAUGAUUGGAGGACCUAUCUUGCCUUCUGAAAGAUCUGGCCAUGCACUGAUUGAGCAGUGGAAUCCCGUAGGCCUGGUUGGAAUCAUCACGGCAUUCAAUUUCCCUGUGGCAGUGUAUGGUUGGAACAACGCCAUCGCCAUGAUCUGUGGAAAUGUCUGCCUCUGGAAAGGAGCUCCAACCACUUCCCUCAUUAGUGUGGCUGUCACAAAGAUAAUAGCCAAGGUUCUGGAGGACAACAAGCUGCCUGGUGCAAUUUGUUCCUUGACUUGUGGUGGAGCAGAUAUUGGCACAGCAAUGGCCAAAGAUGAACGAGUGAACCUGCUGUCCUUCACUGGGAGCACUCAGGUGGGAAAACAGGUGGGCCUGAUGGUGCAGGAGAGGUUUGGGAGAAGUCUGUUGGAACUUGGAGGAAACAAUGCCAUUAUUGCCUUUGAAGAUGCAGACCUCAGCUUAGUUGUUCCAUCAGCUCUCUUCGCUGCUGUGGGAACAGCUGGCCAGAGGUGUACCACUGCGAGGCGACUGUUUAUACAUGAAAGCAUCCAUGAUGAGGUUGUAAACAGACUUAAAAAGGCCUAUGCACAGAUCCGAGUUGGGAACCCAUGGGACCCUAAUGUUCUCUAUGGGCCACUCCACACCAAGCAGGCAGUGAGCAUGUUUCUUGGAGCAGUGGAAGAAGCAAAGAAAGAAGGUGGCACAGUGGUCUAUGGGGGCAAGGUUAUGGAUCGCCCUGGAAAUUAUGUAGAACCGACAAUUGUGACAGGUCUUGGCCACGAUGCGUCCAUUGCACACACAGAGACUUUUGCUCCGAUUCUCUAUGUCUUUAAAUUCAAGAAUGAAGAAGAGGUCUUUGCAUGGAAUAAUGAAGUAAAACAGGGACUUUCAAGUAGCAUCUUUACCAAAGAUCUGGGCAGAAUCUUUCGCUGGCUUGGACCUAAAGGAUCAGACUGUGGCAUUGUAAAUGUCAACAUUCCAACAAGUGGGGCUGAGAUUGGAGGUGCCUUUGGAGGAGAAAAGCACACUGGUGGUGGCAGGGAGUCUGGCAGUGAUGCCUGGAAACAGUACAUGAGAAGGUCUACUUGUACUAUCAACUACAGUAAAGACCUUCCUCUGGCCCAAGGAAUCAAGUUUCAGUAAAGGUGUUUUAGAUGAACAUCCCUUAAUUUGAGGUGUUCCAGCAGCUGUUUUUGGAGAAGACAAAGAAAAUUAAAGUUUUCCCUGAAUAAAUGCAUUAUUAUGACUGUGACAGUGACUAAUCCCCCUAUGACCCCAAAGCCCUGAUUAAAUCAAGAGAUUCCUUUUUUAAAAAUCAAAAUAAAAUUGUUACAACAUAGCCAUAGUUACUAAAAGAUGAGUUAGGUGGAUUUUUAUUAUGUCAACUAGUUGUACAUGGCUUUUUAAAAGUUAAUGAUUAUUUUGUAAUUAGAAAAAAAUAGUACGUACCAGGGUAGGAAUUUGGGAAAAUACAGAACCGAGGAGAAAACAGAAGUCUUUGCAGUAGAUACAGGGUGUCUCCUGACCAAGUGAAGGAUUCAGGGGCGGGGGGUGAAUAUUGCUUGACAUUACCCACCUAUGGCAUGUGUUGGAUGUCGUGUGAUUGAAAGGGGGAUGCAUUCCCCUGUAUGCUUGGACCACAGUUCAGUAUUCAUGUGGAAUAACUUGCAGUGCUUAAAAUGACAACAGGCAUUCAUCACAGUUAUGGCUCUUGCUUAUGAAGGCUGUGUCAACUUGGAAGAGAUUUCUGGGGUAGACAGAUUUUGUUCCUGUGCUGGAGUCUGCCACCUGCUGGAGGACUCUGAGGCCAAAAUUGCCCGUGCAGAGUUGUAUAGAAAAUGCGUCUGGAGGCUGGGCAAGGUGGCUUACGCCUAUAAUCCCAGCACUUUGAGAGGCCGAGGCGGGUGGAUCAGUAGAGGCUAGGAGUUUGAGACCAGCCUGGCCGAUAUCGUGAAACCCCGUCUUUACCAAAAAAUACAAAAAUUAGCCCAGUGUGGUGGCAGGCACCUGUAAUCCCAGCUAUUAGGGAGGCUGAGGCAGGAGAAUUGUGUGAACCCAGGAGGCAGAGGUUGCAGUGAGCCUAGAUUGUGCCACUGCCUGGGCAACAGUGAGAUCCUGUCUACAAAAAAAAAAAAAAAAAAAAGUGCAUCUGGAUUUUUUUAUACAACCUUAGACCACCUUCUUUAGCUUUAGGCGUCUGCGGUUGCCCUUGGAUCUGUUCUCAAUCCUCAGUGUGUGUGGCAGCAUGUGGUCAUAGAGAGCUGGGCAAAGUUCACUUUCUCUUUGCUGACAGUCUCACCUUUUCUCACUGGGAAGCUGCACAGGAGCCUUUGGGCUGGUUCAGCCCAGAGGCCCCUGUUCUCCUGCCUUCCUGGCAUUCUCUGCUCCCCUUCUGCAUGGCACCCCUCUACUCCUGCCAGGUUAGAAUGGAGCAGAGGCCUUUGAACAAGAUGACAUUUGUAGACAACCUGAUCCAUCAGGAUGUGGAGAGAUCUGGACAAAUGGCAAAUAAUUUGGGGUUGAAUUAUGGCCCAGAGAAGUAAGCAAAUGAAAAACUAAACAAUUAUAAAUGUAUCUGGGAAGCAAAGGUAUUCAUAAUAUGUCCCAUGGCCAGCUGCGAGCAGUAUUUAACUAGACAUGCUGUUGUCAAUAUUGAACAUGAAUCAAGCCAAAUACUGAUAUAGCUAUUGAGAGAAGGUUGGCAGGAAGAAAUCAUGGGUGAGGGUAUGUGGGAGUGAUAAUCUUAGCUAUAGAUUUUAGGUAAAACUGAUUCUGAAAGCUUUCUUUGAAACAAAUUUAUAAUUUUUCUUCUACAUGUUUCUAGCACAAGGACUCAAUUUUUUUUGGUUAUAAUGUUCAUUAAAACAUAUGCCUUCAAUUUGUUCCUCUUUGUUCUUUUUUGCUGAUUUAGCAGAUAUAAAUCACUUGUUAGUAUUUUUAACUAUCCAAGUUAAAAUGUACAUUUGUAAGUGUUAUUACUGGUCUUAUAUUUGAAGGUGCAAGGGGUCUUGUGCUGCUCAUUACUGGUUAUCUUGAGCAUUUCAUAACUGCUGCCUCCUCCUAAAUCCUGUGUUCCAACCGCUACUGCUGGCAAUGCCCAGCCUCCAUUGUGGAUGCGGGGAAUUGUGUUCAGCAUGCUUGCUUCUGCCACGGCACUAAAGCCUAACUUGCUUAGGAUCUUGCUGUACUUGGAGAGAGCAUCCAUUCGCUGAGCCUAGCAGCCAGGCUCUUGUGACUCCCUGGGAAGUGGGUGAAGACCUGGCUCCUGGCUGCAGCAGUGAGGAGGCAGGCCCUCCAGGUGAAGACUUCUCACAAUGGAGGGAAGGCAGUUUUCUCAAAGGAAAUUGAGUGCUAUUAUGUACUCUGCUUCCUACUUUCUCUUUCAGGGUGGGAAUCUGUUAAGCCUCCUCUCUCUCUUGCUCUGCAACCACAGAACACUUCUUUUUUUUUGGUGUCUCAGUUUUGCCCACACUGGAGUGCAGUGGUGCAAUAGUGGCUCACUGCAGCCUCCAACUCCUGGGCUCAAUCUAUCCUUCCACCUCAUGCUCCCCAGUAGCUGGGACUACAGGUGCAUGCCACUGUGCCCAGCUGAUUAUUAUUUUUUUUUGUAAAGAUUGGGUCAUACUACAUUGCUCAUGCUCGUCUUGAACUUGUGGCCUCAAGCGAUCCUCCUGCCUCAGCCUCUUGAGUUGUUGGGAUUACAGGAGUGUGCCACCAUGCCCAGCUCUGUGGAAAAUUCUCUGUGGCAUUCUGUCUCCUGAAAAUGCUGAAGGGACCAAGAGGGCUCUGUGUCCUUCCUCUUCUCUUCCCUGGCACUUUCAGACCAUUUUCUUGUUGCCUUCAUUCUAACAAAGGUUGCAGAUUGGAAAGCUGAUUUGGAAUGCUUUUUAAGUGUUUUCAGUUUCAAUAUUUUUAUGAAAUUCCUAUGGUCUCCAACAAACUUUUUUUUUUUUUUUUUUUUCUACACCUGGAGCUUAUCCUGCAGAAGCUUCCUGCCAAUGAUUGUUUUGGAGGAAAUUAAAAGAAAACCAAACGAAACCUCUCCUAUCCAAGGGGAAGAACUUUAUCCCCAUAUUGAUUGAAUAUAGGAUUCUAGAUUUAAAAUGUUGUAGGCAGUUAGAGUUUGCUCUUUUUUUUUUUCUAUUGGAAAGGUCCACAAAUGUUUUAUUGACAUUUUUGUCUUUAAUCCAUUUGGAUUUGGGGUACAUGUUACGAUUUGUCUACGUUAAUUUCCCUUUUAAAAAUAAAAAUAAUUCCUCAACUCCAA